AAUGGAUUUGCUUAAAAUUUCUCACACAAAGCUACAUUUACUGGAGGAUCUUUCUAUAAAAAAUAAACAGAGGAUGUCAAACUUGGCACAAUUUGACUCUGAUUUUUACCAAUCUAAUUUUACUAUUGAUAACCAGGAGCAGAGUGGUAAUGACUCUAAUGCCUAUGGAAAUCUUUAUGGAUCUAGAAAACAACAAGCUGGUGAGCAGCCUCAGCCUGCCUCCUUUGUUCCAUCAGAGAUGCUCAUGUCAUCGGGUUACGCAGGACAAUUUUUUCAGCCAGCAUCCAACUCAGAUUAUUAUUCACAAUCUCCUUACAUUGACAGUUUUGAUGAAGAGCCUCCUUUGCUAGAAGAUAAGUUAAGGAAGUGUUAUUAAUGUGUGUACAGCUAGAAGAAUAAUAGCAAUAAUUAGCACUUAAUGUGUGCUGUCAGCCUGCAGUGUACAGUGUCUUAUGUUUGAUUGUUUCACAUAUAACAAGAGUUUGCUGAACCAAAACCCUUAAACCAUUGGAAGUUUGUUGCAUGUUUGCAUAGGGGAAAUUGGGUGCAGAUAUGAGAUAUUCUGUGAUAUUGCUGCACCUAUUAAAUGCUCCUUCACUCUUUCUUAAAUUCGAACUCCUUGGCCAAGAAUAGAAAAAAAUGAAGACAUCUUUUGGCAGAGUAGUUACAUCAAAGUGACCACCCUUCCCACCCUGUUAAUGAAGCACUUCAUAACAGCGUAUUUUAUUUUCUGCUAUGUUUUCCUGGGAGCAAAGUGGAUAUUUUCUCAAAUUAAUAUUUUUUGUUGUCAUUGUUGACAUGGAGACAAGCCAGUUUUUUUUCUUUCCUGACUCAUACAAGCCCUUUCAUAUCAGCUUGGCAUGGGUAGGUGAGGAAGAACAUAAAUCCAGUAAAUAAUGCUGCUGGUGGGAAGGAAAUCCAGACAUUCUUGGAACUGAAGGUACUUAGGGGAUUUCGGAGUUGUUCCAUCCAUUGAUUUUUUUUUUUCAUAUGUAGCCAGUCUGUAUGUGCUGUUUUUGCUCUUAAACAAUGUUAAUACAAUGCUGGAAACAUAGGCGUUAAGACGCUAAAACCCAAGUGGAUUUAAAUUGGAGAACCAAGCAGAAAUAGUCACUGGUUAACUACUCCAAGUCCUUUGCAUGUAGUCAAGUGAAAAGGAAUAGAUUAAAAUUUCCAGUAUUUUACAUCACAAGAUGUAAAGGUGUUUGCCUCACAUGAACACAACCAGCCACAUUCUUCUUUCUUUUCCUUAAAAAUAUAAAAACAUGAAAGAUUUAAACUGUUCAGAACAGAACAGAGAUUUAUAUAAUCGAUCUAUUGGCUCUUUAGAAGCCAGUCAAGUUUCUGGAUCAGUUAUCUUUAACCAGUUCAUUCAGUUUUGCCUCUACAAGUAAUAAACACCUAGAAGUUACAAGUUAUUCUUGUUAAACAUUUUCCUUGACUUUGCCAAUAUCUCUCCCUAAUUGUCUUCAGAAUUUGGAAAACAUAGAAACAUAAGAAUAAAAAUAUAAAAAUUACUUCAAUUCUUGUCUCAAAGACAUGACUAUCAUUAACAAUUUGAUGUAUUUUCUUCUAGCCUUUAUUCUAUUUUCCUAUAAAUGCCUGUGUAUAUGUAUUAUGUAUGAAUAUACAUGCAUACUUUAAAGUAAAAUACUAUUUUUUCAAUGAAUAUAUAUGCAUCUGAGUACUUAAGUAUUAUAUUCUUUUUAUUUACUUUAUGUCACGAGUAUUUUUUUUCUUUUUGAGAUGGAGUCUUACUCUGUUGCCGAGGCUGGAGUGCAGUGGCCCAAUCUCAGCUCUCUGCAACCUCUGCCUCCCGGGUUCAAGCGAUCCUCCCCCUCAGCCUCCUGAGUAGUUGAGACUACAGGUGCACACCACCGUGCAUGGCUAAUUUUUGUGUUUUUAGUAGAGACAGGGCUUUGCCAUGUUGUCAAGGCUAGUCUCGACCUCCUGACUUUGGGUGAUCCACCCGCUUCAGCCUCCCAAAAUGCUGGGAUUACGGGCAUGAGCCACUGUGCCCAGCCUGUCACGAGCACUUCUAUGCAAGCAUUCUUUAAAGUCAUUAAAUAUUAUUUGAAAACAAUUUAUAAUGGUUUCACAGAGUUCUAUCAUAUAACAUAACCGUAAUUUAAACACGCCUUAAAGGUUAUUCCUUAUAGCAAGUAAUGCUUUGUUGACCAUCAUAGGAAACCAUCUUUGACCUUUAUAGAGUCUGUCCUUAGGAUGUACCCAUAACAGUGGGAUUGCUGGGUUAAAGGUACUGACACUGUCAACUGAUCUCAAAAAUGGUGUUCUACUCCACUUCCAGAGUAGAAUAUGACAUGUCUUUGUCAAUUUUGUAGGAAAAAAGGAAAAAGGAAUACUUUGUACCUCUGGGUUACUAAAAAAAUUUUGACAUUUCUCAUAUAUGUAUUGACUUUUUAUUUUUCAUGGGUUUUUUUGUUCAGAUUUCUAUAGAAUCUAAAGAGUUUUCUUUCCUCGUUUAUUUUUUAGGGAUUUUAUAUAGUAACCAUAUUAAUUAUUGCCUAGAAUGUGCAUUUUAAACUUUUUUUUUCCUAGCUUGUGUUUGCCACCUAAUUUGUUUAUGGGUCUUUGGGACAUAUUAAAAAUGUGAUAUUAAUUUUUUAAACCCAGCAUAUCUUUUCUAGUAACAUUUCUUUCCAAUUGUUCUUUGUUUAGAGUCUAUUUCUCCAGCUCUAAGUACUGCCUCUAUCUCCUUAUAGAUGCUCACAUUUUAAAAUUAUCCUUUUAUGUUUUUUGUUUUAUAUUGAAAUUUUUUAUUCAAUAGUUGUUUAAGCUUAAUAUGUGAAGUAAGGAUUUAUUUAUUUUUUCUGUGCUGCUUAACUAAUUUUUUUCCUGCAGCAUUUGUUGAAAGUAAUCUUUUCUACUAUCUGAAAUGUCUCUAUUGUUGCAUUAAUUUACCACUUUCUAUACAUCCUCCUCUAACAUGUCUUUCAAUUUGAAUAGAAAAUAUGUAAUAGAUUUUUAUUUCCAUUUUAUACAGCUCAGAGUUAAUUUCCCCAAAAUACAUAGUGUAUUAGAACAGCAGUCCCCAACCUUUUUGGCACCAGGGAACAGUUUUGUGGAAGACAAUUUUUCCACAGCCAGGUUGGGGAGAUGAUUUUGAGAUGAAACUCUUCCACUUCAGAUCAUCAGGCAUUAGUUAGAUUCUCAUAACAAGCGUGCAGCCUAGAUCCUUUGCAUGCACAGUUCAUAAUAGGGUUCACGCUCCUAUGAGAAACUAAUGCAGCUCAUCUGGCAGGAGGCGGAGCUAAGGUGAUAAUACUUGUUCGCCCACUGCCCACUGCUCACCUCCACCUCCUGCUGUGCGGCCCGGUUCCUAACAGGCCAUGGGCAGGUAGAUAUGGGUCCACGGCCCGGGGAUUGGGGACACCUGUAUUAGAAGAUAGAGUACCUAAUAUAAUUUUGUGCUUUGAAUCUAUGAAAUAUCUGGAUUUUGGAUCCAAUGUGUUCUUCAAGCUGAGUGACUUGUGAAAGCCUCAAGCCUCUUUUGUCUAAAGAUAUGAAAAAGGCCAGGGUAUGUCUUUUUCAGAUAUAAAAAAAAUACAAUUUCUAGGAUAACGCAUUAAAUAACAUUUACUAGUUUUUAUUGACAAUCCAACAGAAUGGCCUAUAAAAUUAUGAAGCUAUAAUACUAUGCACAAAAAUGUGUUGUUUCAAAAGUGUCCUACUUUAUUUCUUAAAUAUUUUGUUGUCUAAAAUAUUUGUUUGGUUUUAUGUAAGAAUGAUAAAUUUUGCUCUUUGUUAAUGUAAAAUCAAUAUGUUAACAAAUGCAUUUUCAAGAAUAAUAAUAAAUUCAAGUCUGUCAGAUACGAAAAA